CUCUCUUCCACAGGAGGCCUACACGCCGCCGCUUGUGCUGCAGCCAUGUCUCUAGUGAUCCCUGAAAAGUUCCAGCAUAUUUUGCGAGUACUCAACACCAACAUCGAUGGGCGGCGGAAAAUAGCCUUUGCCAUCACUGCCAUUAAGGGUGUGGGCCGAAGAUAUGCUCAUGUGGUGUUGAGGAAAGCAGACAUUGACCUCACCAAGAGGGCGGGAGAACUCACUGAGGAUGAGGUGGAACGUGUGAUCACCAUUAUGCAGAAUCCACGCCAGUACAAGAUCCCAGACUGGUUCUUGAACAGACAGAAGGAUGUAAAGGAUGGAAAAUACAGCCAGGUCCUAGCCAAUGGUCUGGACAACAAGCUCCGUGAAGACCUGGAGCGACUGAAGAAGAUUCGGGCCCAUAGAGGGCUGCGUCACUUCUGGGGCCUUCGUGUCCGAGGCCAGCACACCAAGACCACUGGCCGCCGUGGCCGCACCGUGGGUGUGUCCAAGAAGAAAUAAGUCUGUAGGCCUUGUCUGUUAAUAAAUAGUUUAUAUACCUAUGGC